GAGACGGGGUGGCGGCUGCAGCCCGGGUAGGGCCAGGAGACCCGGUCCACGUUUGCAAACGCAGCCGAACGCCCAGGCCGACCCGUGCCGCCCGAGCGCCGCGCUGCGUCCGCGCCACUCUUCUCGCCGCCCCGAUGGCGUUCCGGGGCUGGAGGCCCCCGCCGCCACCGCUGCUCCUGCUGCUGCUCUGGGUGACCGGGCAGGCAGCGCCCGUGGCGGGCCUGGGCUCCGACGCGGAGCUGCAGAUCGAGCGGCGCUUCGUGCCCGACGAGUGCCCGCGCACCGUGCGCAGCGGCGACUUCGUGCGCUACCACUACGUGGGGACGUUCCCCGACGGCCAGAAGUUCGACUCCAGCUAUGACAGAGACUCCACUUUCAAUGUGUUUGUGGGAAAAGGACAGCUGAUCACAGGGAUGGACCAGGCUCUUGUUGGGAUGUGCGUAAACGAGAGACGUUUCGUGAAGAUUCCCCCAAAGCUUGCCUACGGAAAUGAAGGAGUUUCUGGUGUGAUCCCCCCCAAUUCAGUGCUUCAUUUUGAUGUACUUCUGAUGGAUAUUUGGAAUUCUGAAGACCAGGUUCAGAUUCACACCUAUUUCAAGCCCCCGAGUUGCCCUCGGACCAUCCAGGUGUCUGAUUUUGUGAGGUACCACUACAACGGGACGUUCCUGGACGGAACUCUGUUUGAUUCGAGUCACAAUCGCAUGAAAACAUAUGACACGUAUGUGGGAAUUGGCUGGCUGAUUCCUGGAAUGGAUAAAGGGCUGCUGGGGAUGUGUGUGGGUGAGAAGCGCAUCAUCACCAUUCCUCCUUUUCUGGCCUAUGGAGAGGAUGGAGAUGGGAAAGACAUUCCCGGUCAGGCAUCUCUGGUGUUUGAUGUUGCAUUAUUGGACCUCCAUAACCCCAAGGACAGCAUUUCCAUUGAGAACAAGGUAGUACCUGAAAACUGUGAGCGGAUAAGUCAAAGUGGGGACUUUCUCAGGUAUCAUUACAAUGGCACGCUUCUGGAUGGCACCCUCUUUGAUUCCAGCUACUCUCGGAACCGCACGUUUGACACGUACAUUGGGCAGGGCUACGUGAUUCCUGGGAUGGAUGAAGGUCUACUUGGUGUUUGCAUUGGAGAAAAGCGAAGGAUUGUGGUCCCGCCUCACCUGGGGUAUGGAGAGGAAGGAAGAGGCGGAGAAACUCCAUCUAUCCAUCCAUCAAAGAUUUAUUGAGUUUCUUCAUGACCAGGCCCUGCUCACGGUGUUAGGGAUUCAGCAGAAAGAAACACAAACAAAACUUCCUACGCACACAGAGAGUGUUUCCUUGUUGACGCCCUCAAUAAUGUGUGUGCCUCAGAGGUUAUCAGGCACCUGGGAGACUGACUCACGUUAACUUCCUAGAAGCUGACAUACUCACCUGAUGCUACAUGGUUCCUUGACUGGGUGUGAAUCGACCUCUACACUGGUUGGAAUUCUUGUGCCUGGAAUCCUCGGGGCCUGAGAGGCUGAGUUCAUUUGACUGCUGACAUCAGAUCCCAGGGAUGUGGGUGGUUCCAGAUGCAUUCCCUUUUGCCCUGGAGAAGGCCCUGCACCUGAAUGCAUCUUGGAGGGGAGAUUAUAUUUGAAUUGAUAAAAUUUGGUGACUGCUUAGCUCAGUGUUAGAAGUUUUUAAAAUUUGUGGUAAAAUAUACUUAACAUCUUUACCUUGUUAACCAUUUUAAGUGUACAGUUUAGUGGCAUCAAAUAUAUUCACAAUGUUGUAUAACCAUUACUAUCAUCUACACUCAGAACUCUUUCAUCAUCCCCAACAUAAACCCAUUACACAAUAACUCCCGAUUCCUCCCUCCUAUCAACCUCUGACAACCACCUUUCUUUCUGUCUCUACCAAUUUGCCUAUUCUAAGUGCCUCACUUGAGUGGAAUCAUACAAUAUUUCUCUUUCUGUGUCUGUCUUAUUUUACUUAGCAUAAUGUUUUCAAGGUCUAUUUGUAUUUUAGCAUUUAUCAAAAUUUCAAGCUGGGCGCGGUGGCUCACGCCUGUAAUCCCAGCACUUUGGGAGGCUGAAGCAGGCGGAUAACCUGAGGUCAGGAGUUCAAGAUCAGCCUGGCCAACAUGGUGAAACCCUGUCUCUACUAAAAACACAAAAAUUAGCCAGGUGUGGUGGUACGCGUCUGUAAUCUCAGCUGAGGCAGGGAAAUCGCUUGAACCCGGGGGACGGAGGUUGCGGUGAGCUGAGAACAUGCCAAUGCACUCCAGCCUGGAUGACAGAGCAAGACUCCAUCUCAAAAAAAAAAAAUUAAUUCCUCAUUUCUGGCUAAUAAAUUUCAUUCCUUUUUAUUGCUGAAUGAAUAUUCCAUUGGAUGUAUAUACUACAUUUUGUUGAUCAGUUCGUCUGGUGAUGAACACUUAGGCUGUUUCUACUUUUUGUCUGUUGUGAAUAAUGCUUAAUGCUUCUGUGAAUAUGAGUGUACAAAUAUCUGUUCGCAUCUCCAGCUUCAAUUCUUUUGUAUAUAUACCCAAGAAAGAUAUUUUUAUUUAAUGUUUUCUUGAAAUAUAAUUCACAUACUAUAAAAAUAAUCAUGUUAAAGUUUACAAUUUAGUUGUUUUUAGUAUAUUAACCAGGUAACAUAACCAUUACCUCUACCUAAUUCCAGCACAGUUUCAUCACUCCAAAAAGUAACCCAUAACCAUUAGCGGUCACUCUCCGUACCCUGUCCUCAUCCAUCCACUUCCCCCACGCUGGCAACAGGUAGUCUAUUUCUUGUCUGUAUGGAUUUGCUUAUGCUGGAUGUUUCCAUAUCCCUGGAAUCCUACAGUAUGUGGCCUUUUGUGUCUGGCUUCUUUCACUUAGCAUAAUGUUUUCGGGUUCAUUCCCAGGUGAUUUUUAACAGGUUACCAAGGUUGAGGAACCAUAGAUCUGCCUCUGCAGACACCCACCCUGUCCAUGUGUGUUAGCUUCCCACACAGAGCCAUCCGUGGCCUGGCUUUGAGCAGCCUUCUGGCCAAUGGCAGGCUGUACUUCCUGGUUCCUGUGGGAAGGAGCCUGCACCCCACUCCACCCACACCAGCAGCCCCUGUUUUGAGUGAGUAGCAGGCACCUGUGUUCUGCUAUUAAAGCACACGCUUCUCAAAUUAUUACCUUUAACUUUGGCCAGCCCCAAAAUUUGUACCUCCAUUUUCUCAGGAUUUUAAUGAGAAUUAAACAAUACAUGUUUAAUUUAGAAGAAUGCCUGGUACUCAAUAAACGCCUAUUAAAUAUGAGCGUGAGUGUGUUUCUAUUAGAGAUAGGAGAGAGACCAAUCAAGAAGCAGACACAGAAAAGUACGUGUUGGGACAGGAGGUAAGGAGGGACUGUUGGAGUUUGUGUAUCUCUAUCUGAAUUUUGUCAUUAGCUGUGUUAUUCUCUUGAAUAAGUAAUAUCAUGUCUGAAUUUUUCAUUUCUUUCUUUCUUUCUUUUUUGAGGACGGAGUCUCACUCUGUUGCCCAGGCUAGAGUACAGUGGUGCAAUCCUAACUCACUGUAGCCUUGACCUCCUGGCCUCAAGCAAUCCUCCUGCCUCAACCUCCCGAGUAUCUGGGACUACAAGUGCUCACCACCACGCCCAGCUAAUUUUUUUGUAGAGACAUUUGGCUGUGUUGCCUAGGCUGGUCUCAAACCCCUGGCCUCAAGUGAUCCUCCCACCUCAGCCUCCCAGAGUUGAGAUUAUAGGCAUGAGCCACCACCAUACCUAACCUGAGUUGGUUUUUUUAUAUGUAAAAUGCUGAUGAUAAUAAAAUAUGUCCUUGACUCUA